CUCGACAGAUCCUGCCGCAGUCCGCUCCCUCCCGCUCCGCUCGCCCCUGCCCGCCCGCCCGCCCGGUCGCGCGGUCGCCGCCGCCACCGUGUCGCCCGCAUCCUCCGCCUGGCGCCUCCGGGCCCCGUGCCUCCGCCCGCCCUCUCCGGCCCCGGCGACGAGGUAACGCGCCCUGGGCCGAGCCGCCGGGCCCUCCGCCCAGAGCGCCGCCCUCCGAGCUCGCCCCGGUGGGUGUGGCCCGGCCUGGCCCGUGCCCCGCUGCCGCACUUCGGUCCCUCCCGAGCCCCGCCGCCGCAUUUCGGCCUCCUCCGGCCGCCCGUAGUUCCAGUUCCCCUUUCCCCACCACGGAGCCCCAGGGCCCCUGGGCUUGUCGAGAUGUCUGAGGCGUCAGGAAAUCUCAACAGCCUCCGCAUGGCGAAUGUGGCCCUGCGCGAAGAAUUAAAUGCCCUUCGCGGGGAGAAUGCCAAUUUGGGCCUCCAGCUCGGGAGAGCCCUGGCCGAGGUUAAUUCCUUGCGGGGCAAUGUCUCCAGCUACAUCCGCUGGCCAGUACCCAUAGUGCCCGUCCUUGCGGAGGAGAACUUGGAGUUCGCGCUCAGUGAGAUCGAAGUCAUUCCCGGGGGAGAACUGCCCUUCUUGUGCCGGCCUCCCCCACGCGCGGAGCCCGACUGUAUCUCGGAUGAUCUUUUGAUUAACGUGAUCCAGGAUCGCAGCACCCCCGACGGGCCCGCUGACCCCCCUCUGCUGCCCAUCCCGCCCCCGCCGGCGCUGCCUCCGCCCGCGUCAAAGGAACCGCCCCCGCAACCCCCUCUGGCACCGCUGGAGCGGCCUGAGAUAGAGCCCUUUUCAGGAGACCCAGUCUACCUGGCUGAAUUCCUGAUGCAGCUAGAGACCUUCAUAGCCGACCAUGAGGUUCAUUUCCCCGGGGGCGCCGAGCGGGUGGCCUUUCUGAUCUCCUUUUUCACUGGCGAAGCCAAGGACUGGGCCAUCUCGGUCACCCAGGAAGGAAGCCCCUUGCAUGCCAACUUCCCGCGCUUCCUGGAUGAAAUCCGUAAGGAAUUCUGUGGCCCCAUCCCCCCACGUGUGGCUAAAAAGGCCAUUCGCAAGCUCAAGCAGGGCCACUGUACCCUCGGCAGCUAUGCAGAUGCUUUUCAGUUCCUGGCCCAAUUCUUGUCUUGGGAUGACUGCCGCCUCCAAAACCAAUUCCUCAAAGGCCUGUCGGAAUUCUUCCGCAAAGAGCUCUUAUGGUCAACAGAAAUGGCCGACCUGGAUGAGCUGAUUCUCGAAUGUGUGGAGAUAGAAAGAAAAGUGCGCGUUCCCAAGCCUAUCCCGCUCCCUGGAGUUCGAAAUAUCAUCUUCCCUUUUGCUCCGAGUCCCAAUGAGGAAGAAAGUGAAGAUGAAGAGUACUACAGUGAAGAUGAAGACCAAGAGGCACGCAGGCACAGGCUUCACUCCAAGGACCAGAGGAAGCGCAUGAGGGCUUUUCAGCAAGAGAUGAAGGAGAAGGAGGAGGAGGAGAUGAAGAAGGAGGAAGAAAUGAAGAAGAAGGAAGAGAAGGAGGAGGAGGAGGAAGAGGAAAUGAAACAGAAAGAGGAGGAGGAGGAGAUAAGGAACAAGAAUGAGGAGGAAGGAGAGAGUAAGGAUGAAGAAGAUGAAGAUGAGGAUGGGGGCCAGAAACCAGAAGGAGAGCCACAGCAGGAUCCAGGGACUGAGGAGACCUAUGGUGAGGUGGAGGAGGAGCCACUGGAUGAGGCCCAAGAUGAUGACCUAGAUGAGCUGAUGGAGAUGGAGCCGACCUUUGUUCACGCGUCAUCCCAGACUUCUGGCCCCACAAGUGGUUACCACGCCGAAAACUUCCUGGGUGCAUCACCUCCCAUAAUACAGCCUAGCAGACGGAGGAACCAGAAUCGAGUCCCACUUCUGGAAGGCCUUCCAGGCACCAAUUCACCAUUCUACAGCUCCCCCCAACUGAUUCGCCGCACAGGUCGUUUAGGACAACGCCAAGUUCGAAGACGCCCCCCUGUGCUUUUCCGCCUCACUCCGAGACAGGGGGGCCACCGAGCUGCUCGUGGCCGAAUUCGAGUUUGAGUGCUGGGGCCAGAUGGCCACCCAGAACACACCCUUCUUUUGCAUCCCCCGCCCCUGCUAUUGCUGCCAUACCUGCCCCAUUUGCUGACCAGGACUUCAGGGAGUUUCAGACCUGCAGAACCUGAAGAAGACCUGCAGAAUUCCAGACCAUCUUGCAACCGUGACCAGAGAGCGACGUGUGCCCAACCAGGGCCACCUGGGAAAGGAGGGAUCAGCAAUAGCUGCCCUCUUGGCAUGUACUCUGCUCAGUCCGGCCACGAGCUGGAGAGCAAGUUUCUGGGCCUGUUCCCAUAAAUGAACUGGUCACCCUCUUGUAUUUCCCCUCUGGUUGUUCCUAACCCUCACCUCUCCUGCGUUUCUUCACCCUAUGUUCUACAGUUUUAUUCUCUGACUGACCCACCAGGACUUCACCCAAUGCCUCACUGAUCUGCCCCAAUGAGCAAGAGGACAGGCUACCCUGAACUCCUAAAGCCACUGAGGCCAGUUGCUAGAUAUAAUCGAUGGUGAGCAGGAUGGUAUCCAGAAAUGUCCCUAGAAUCCUACACUCAUUUCAUGCCACACCUCCAGCAGAGGGCCUGGAAGAGGACCCGACAUCUAGCCCAGUGAGAGUGUGCAAAGCCACAUGUCAAAUGGACAACUUGACGGAGAUUUGCCCUUGACUGACUGUGCAGGCUGGUUCCACUUACAGCACUUGAGUUUACCUUUGCACAGAUUCCUGUAUCAGGGCUCUUGGACUGACUUGCCACACAUCUGGAGCCCUUUCCUCUCACCACAUUGCCCUCCUGGGCACCCCCGGUGGACAGCGCCCAACAUUGCAGGCUCCACAACUUUCCUUGAUGUUGCCUAAAGGGUAGCCAGUUAGGGUUCCGGAGAGGAGAAGGAGGAAGAAGAGGAGGAGGAGAAAGAAGCAGCAACGAUCAUUCUGCCAUUGUAAAGAGUGACUCUUUCCUUAGGGAUGGUGGUCUUCUCCCCUUGCCAGGCCUUGGACUGCAGCCCCCAGUCAAAGGUCUUUGCAGGACACUUUCUAUCCUUGGAGUUGCAGAGGAGGCCUGAUUGGCCAUUCCUUCUGGGACAGACAGAGAGAGGGCCCAUGGCCUGCUCUGAGCUCCCUUCAAUUUCAAGGAACCCUUAGUUCUGAGAGGAGAGAGGAAGGCUGCACCUACCGUGGCCUCACAGCUGGGACCCCUCAUGGGGGCCAACCCCUGGCCUGCUGCUGUGCUUCAGUGACACAGUAAAGCUUAAGAGGGUGGCUGCCUCCUAGGAACUCCUGGGACUUCUAGGUACAAACUCAGGUGCCCUUAUAAAGAGACCCACUGCUUGCCUUGAGUCCAGAAAGCACUGCUUCUGCAGUGAAAAACACACACUUACUAUGUCAGUUUUGGCCAUAAAAUGCCAGCCAAAUCCACUGCUGGCCUGAACUGCCCCUGGACACUGGACUUUCUGCACAGUGACUGGCAGCAGAGCAAGUGCAGCCAGGGUUUGUGGCCAAAGGGAAGAAAGCAUAGUAAAUUCAACCUCUGUUCCUCAUGGGAGUCUGACCGAUAAUCUCAGGCGGACCUUAGGAUCUUGGGCCUGGAGGCAAGAGAAAAAAGCUGGAGGAAGAGGAGUCGCAGAGAAACCCAGUCCUCUGACUGGUUUCUGGUGAGGUCUCUAUUCAUCAGUGGGAGGUAAGAUGCCCUUUUCAUUAGCGCUUUUGUUUCUCAGCCUGGGGAUCAGUGGAUUUGGAUUCCUAUAACCUGUUGCUACCUUUUAAAAAGAUCCCCUCUCUCCAAAGAGAAAAGUAAUACAUAAUCAUUAAAGAAAGUUUGGAAAAUAGAGAAAACUAUGAGGACAAAAACCCCCCAGCCAUUCAGAGUCCCACCACACAGAGGCAAGCACUAUUAACACUUUGCUGCUUUCCUUUCUAGUGUGUUCUUGCUAUGUCUUGUCAAAGCUGAGAUCACCCUGCCAGUUCUUGAUCAGCAGGAUUUAAAAUGGCUGCCACCUGUGCAGUCAUGCAUACUGAAUAAUUCAUUUAAGCAUUCUCCUAAUUUGUUGGACCUUUCAAUUGUCUGGUUUUCCCCAUCCCCACCAGGGCAGGAGUAAACAACUUUGUAAAGAAAAUUUUGUCUGUUUUUCAGCUGAUUUUAUCUGAUUUCCUCAAGAGUGCAUUCCAGAAGGGGACCUGCUAUUCUUCGAGGGGACCUGCUAUUCUUCGAGGCAGUGGACCCUGUUUGCUGAUGGUCAACACUCUGGCCCUGCUGCCCCAUGUCCCUGUGGAGAAGUGUGAAGGACGGGUGCCUUAAACCCACACUUCCAGGGACCCUUCAGCACAGGUCCUGCCUGUUCCCAUGGUGCUUCUCACCCUGAACCCUCAGAGCUACAGCCAGGGAUAGAGCAGAUGAGCAGUGAGCUGGUUUCCACCCUCUGGGGCAGGAGGGGCUUGGGCUUCCCUUUGACCCUCUUCCUUCCUUUCCCAGAUCUUCAAUAUUUGUUGUGAUGUAACAGCCAUAAGAGCUGUAAGAGGAACUGUGGGCUUUGGGAGCUUUCUUGGGUUGAAAGAGGGGUGGGGGGAGGGGAUGCAUGCAGGGGUAUGAAGGCAGCCCAAGGUCUCCCAGAGGCUCGGGAGGAAACCCUUUUGGAAUACAUGUGUUAUUGUUGCAUUACUGUGUUGUGAAGAUAAGAAGCUGCUCUGUAUGCUAAAGCUUUCUCUCCUCAAUAAAAAUAUAAAGGGUGUGUAAA